UAGAGAUGGGGUCUUCCUAUGUUGCCCACUUUGGUUUGUUAGUUUUAGUAGUUUAUAAUUCCUUUGUAUUAUUGUGAACAAAUAACAGUUAUUUUGAAAUAGAAGAGUGCUUUCUAUUUAAAAUUUUGCUUUGAUAGGGUUCUGUCUACUUUCUGAGCCUUACCUUCCUGUGCAUUCCCCUUUGGUCAGUACCAUCUUACCACACAGGCUGCUUUUAGUUUCUUGAGUUAUCCAUCUUCCUUCUAUCUUAUAGGGCUCAACCUAAAUAUUACUCAGGGAAGCCUUCCUUGAGAGUCUUUCUUUUUGCACUCAUUGGUUUGGGGCUUCUUUAUAUUAUACUGUUAAUUGAAUUCUGAGUCGUGUUUAUCUCAACUGAGAUUAGGUAAUUUAUUUUGAGAACAGUAAAUGUUUAUCAUCUGUCAUUCUUUUUUUCAUGCCCACAUUCAGUUAUUUGUAAGUGCUGAAUGUAUAAGUGUUCAUCUACAGAUAAGGAUCAGUUCUUUUUUCCCCAACUAGAAAUGUUACUCCAGUUGAUAAUAACAGCUCAAACGGAAAUAUAAGGCAGAGGUGAGAGAGUCACUUGAGGCCACGAAUUGGAGACCAGCCUGGGCAACAAAGUGAGACCUUAUCCCUAUGAAAAAUAAAAUUAGCCCAGCUUGGGAGGCUGAGGUGGGGGGAUUGCUUGAACCCUGGAGUUCCAGGCUGCAGUGAGUUGUUAUCACACCACUGCACUCCAGCCGCGGUGACAGACCCUGUCCCUUAAAAAAAAAAAAAUUAUAACCAGCCACAUUGAAAUAUUUUGUAAGACAUUAAUAGAAGACUAAAUGUUCUCAUAUGUUUACUGUUUGUGUUAAGUACGUAUGGUUUUUAGAACAACAGUUUUCUAUCAAGUGUGGUCUGGUUCACUUAGAAUUAGAUGGGGUAGAUUUUUUGAAAAGCGUUUUGAAGUUAAAUUAGAAGCUAAUGGUUUUUUGUCACUAAAUCAAAUUUUGUUUUAUGCGUUUAAGUGCUACAUUUAUUUGAUAGGCAGGUGAAUGUAACAGAUUAAACUUGAAAAUAAUGUAGCUAUGAUUCCUUCAAGGAAAAACCCACCUACCUUUAGUUCUUUUAGUAUAUUGCAUUAUAAGUCUUUUGUGUGUGCAUAUAUAGCAGGCAUAAAUUGGCAUAAUUCUGGGUUUAAUUUUAGGCUAGGCGCUAUGGAAGUUUGAACUCUAAUUACAGUGUAAAAAUAACCCAGAGGAAAAUUUCAGAAUAAUAAAUCAUUGGGACUAUAUGGUACAGAUGUCCCUGUUUUCAGAUUGUAGAAUUGUUGACCAGUAGGAAUGCUUUAUGAUUAAAAGCCAGGAAAUUAAAGUAAUUCUGAUGAUUUGGUAUUUCUAAAGAUUUUCAUAGAUGACAGUUGAGAACUACUCUCAGAUGAGAUUCUUCCAUUGCUGGGUAAAUACCUUAAAUUGGAAUUACUGGGUCACAUGAGGGGAGGUAUGGUGUCAAGAAAACAUAGUCACCAUUAUUACGAAAAGUAAAAUAUGGAAGAGAUGAUCCCUACCAUCAAUCAGCUUACAACUAGAGGCACUGACAAAUGUAUACAGAUAGCUGUAAUGUAAGGUUAAAAAUCUGUAAGAGCCUGAUUUUAGAAUUCACCAGCUCCUCAGAAGUUUGGCGAAAUAUGAGUUAUUAAGCCUACGCUCAGAUCAAGGUAGCAGCUAGACUGGUGUGACAACCUGUUUUUAAUCAGUGACUCAAAGCUGUGAUCACCCUGAUGUCACCGAAUGGCCACAGCUUGUAAAAGAGAGUUACAGUGGAGGUAAAAGGAGUGGCUUGCAGGAUGGAGAAGCUGCACCAGUGUUAUUGGAAAUCAGGAGAACCUCAGUCUGACGACAUUGAAGCUAGCCGAAUGAAGCGAGCAGCUGCAAAGCAUCUAAUAGAACGCUACUACCACCAGUUAACUGAGGGCUGUGGAAAUGAAGCCUGCACGAAUGAGUUUUGUGCUUCCUGUCCAACUUUUCUUCGUAUGGAUAAUAAUGCAGCAGCUAUUAAAGCCCUCGAGCUUUAUAAGAUUAAUGCAAAACUCUGUGAUCCUCAUCCCUCCAAGAAAGGAGCAAGCUCAGCUUACCUUGAGAACUCGAAAGGUGCCCCCAACAACUCCUGCUCUGAGAUAAAAAUGAACAAGAAAGGCGCUAGAAUUGAUUUUAAAGAUGUGACUUACUUAACAGAAGAGAAGGUAUAUGAAAUUCUUGAAUUAUGUAGAGAAAGAGAGGAUUAUUCCCCUUUAAUCCGUGUUAUUGGAAGAGUUUUUUCUAGUGCUGAGGCAUUGGUACAGAGCUUCCGGAAAGUUAAACAACACACCAAGGAAGAACUGAAAUCUCUUCAAGCAAAAGAUGAAGACAAAGAUGAAGAUGAAAAGGAAAAAGCUGCAUGUUCUGCUGCUGCUAUGGAAGAAGACUCAGAAGCAUCUUCCUCAAGGAUAGGUGAUAGCUCACAGGGAGACAACAAUUUGCAAAAAUUAGGCCCUGAUGAUGUGUCUGUGGAUAUUGAUGCCAUUAGAAGGGUCUACACCAGAUUGCUCUCUAAUGAAAAAAUUGAAACUGCCUUUCUCAAUGCACUUGUAUAUUUGUCACCUAACGUGGAAUGUGACUUGACGUAUCACAAUGUAUACUCUCGAGAUCCUAAUUAUCUGAAUUUGUUCAUUAUCGUAAUGGAGAAUAGAAAUCUCCACAGUCCUGAAUAUCUGGAAAUGGCUUUGCCAUUAUUUUGCAAAGCGAUGAGCAAGCUACCCCUUGCAGCCCAAGGAAAACUGAUCAGACUGUGGUCUAAAUACAAUGCAGACCAGAUUCGGAGAAUGAUGGAGACAUUUCAGCAACUUAUUACUUAUAAAGUCAUAAGCAAUGAAUUUAACAGUCGAAAUCUAGUGAAUGAUGAUGAUGCCAUUGUUGCUGCUUCGAAGUGCUUGAAAAUGGUUUACUAUGCAAAUGUAGUGGGAGGGGAAGUGGACACAAAUCACAAUGAAGAAGAUGAUGAAGAGCCCAUCCCUGAGUCCAGCGAGCUGACACUUCAGGAACUUUUGGGAGAAGAAAGAAGAAACAAGAAAGGUCCUCGAGUGGACCCCCUGGAAACUGAACUUGGUGUUAAAACCCUGGAUUGUCGAAAACCACUUAUCCCUUUUGAAGAGUUUAUUAAUGAACCACUGAAUGAGGUUCUAGAAAUGGAUAAAGAUUAUACUUUUUUCAAAGUAGAAACAGAGAACAAAUUCUCUUUUAUGACAUGUCCCUUUAUAUUGAAUGCUGUCACAAAGAAUUUGGGAUUAUAUUAUGACAAUAGAAUUCGCAUGUACAGUGAACGAAGAAUCACUGUUCUCUACAGCUUAGUUCAAGGACAGCAGUUGAAUCCAUAUUUGAGACUCAAAGUUAGACGUGACCAUAUCAUAGAUGAUGCACUUGUCCGGCUAGAGAUGAUCGCUAUGGAAAAUCCUGCAGACUUGAAGAAGCAGUUGUAUGUGGAAUUUGAAGGAGAACAAGGAGUUGAUGAGGGAGGUGUUUCCAAAGAAUUUUUUCAGCUGGUUGUGGAGGAAAUCUUCAAUCCAGAUAUUGGUAUGUUCACAUACGAUGAAUCUACAAAAUUGUUUUGGUUUAAUCCAUCUUCUUUUGAAACUGAGGGUCAGUUUACUCUGAUUGGCAUAGUACUGGGUCUGGCUAUUUACAAUAACUGUAUACUGGAUGUACAUUUUCCCAUGGUUGUCUACAGGAAGCUAAUGGGGAAAAAAGGAACUUUUCGUGACUUGGGAGACUCUCACCCAGUUCUAUAUCAGAGUUUAAAAGAUUUAUUGGAGUAUGAAGGGAAUGUGGAAGAUGACAUGAUGAUCACUUUCCAGAUAUCACAGACAGAUCUUUUUGGUAACCCAAUGAUGUAUGAUCUAAAGGAAAAUGGUGAUAAAAUUCCAAUUACAAAUGAAAACAGGAAGGAAUUUGUCAAUCUUUAUUCUGACUACAUUCUCAAUAAAUCAGUAGAAAAACAGUUCAAGGCUUUUCGGAGAGGUUUUCAUAUGGUGACCAAUGAAUCUCCCUUAAAGUACUUAUUCAGACCAGAAGAAAUUGAAUUGCUUAUAUGUGGAAGCCGGAAUCUAGAUUUCCAAGCACUAGAAGAAACUACAGAAUAUGACGGUGGCUAUACCAGGGACUCUGUUCUGAUUAGGGAGUUCUGGGAAAUCGUUCAUUCAUUUACAGAUGAACAGAAAAGACUCUUCUUGCAGUUUACAACGGGCACAGACAGAGCACCUGUGGGAGGACUAGGAAAAUUAAAGAUGAUUAUAGCCAAAAAUGGCCCAGACACAGAAAGGUUACCUACAUCUCAUACUUGCUUUAAUGUGCUUUUACUUCCGGAAUACUCAAGCAAAGAAAAACUUAAAGAGAGAUUGUUGAAGGCCAUCACGUAUGCCAAAGGAUUUGGCAUGCUGUAAAACAAAACAAAACAAAAUAAAACAAAAAAAAGGAAGGAAAAAAAAAGAAAAAAUUUAAAAAAUUUUAAAAAUAUAACGAGGGAUAAAUUUUUGGUGGUGAUAGUGUCCCAGUACAAAAAGGCUGUAAGAUAGUCAACCACAGUAGUCACCUAUGUCUGUGCCUCCCUUCUUUAUUGGGGACAUGUGGGCUGGAACAGCAGAUUUCAGCUACAUAUAUGAACAAAUCCUUUAUUAUUAUUAUAAUUAUUUUUUUGCGUGAAAGUGUUACAUAUUCUUUCACUUGUAUGUACAGAGAGGUUUUUCUGAAUAUUUAUUUUAAGGGUUAAAUCACUUUUGCUUGUGUUUAUUACUGCUUGAGGUUGAGCCUUUUGAGUAUUUAAAAAAUAUAUACCAACAGAACUACUCUCCCAAGGAAAAUAUUGCCACCAUUUGUAGACCACGUAACCUUCAAGUAUGUGCUACUUUUUUGUCCCUGUAUCUAACUCAAAUCAGGAACUGUAUUUUUUUUAAUGAUUUGCUUUUGAAACUUGAAGUCUUGAAAACAGUGUGAUGCAAUUACUGCUGUUCUAGCCCCCAAAGAGUUUUCUGUGCAAAAUCUUGAGAAUCAAUCAAUAAAGAAAGAUGGAAGGAAGGGAGAAAUUGGAAUGUUUUAACUGCAGCCCUCAGAACUUUAGUAACAGCACAACAAAUUAAAAACAAAAACAACUCAUGCCACAGUAUGUCGUCUUCAUGUGUCUUGCAAUGAACUGUUUCAGUAGCCAAUCCUCUUUCUUAGUAUAUGAAAGGACAGGGAUUUUUGUUCUUGUUGUUCUCGUUGUUGUUUUAAGUUUACUGGGGAAAGUGCAUUUGGCCAAAUGAAAUGGUAGUCAAGCCUAUUGCAACAAAGUUAGGAAGUUUGUUGUUUGUUUAUUAUAAACAAAAAGCAUGUGAAAGUGCACUUAAGAUAGAGUUUUUAUUAAUUACUUACUUAUUACCUAGAUUUUAAAUAGACAAUCCAAAGUCUCCCCUUCGUGUUGCCAUCAUCUUGUUGAAUCAGCCAUUUUAUCGAGGCACGUGAUCAGUGUUGCAACAUAAUGAAAAAGAUGGCUACUGUGCCUUGUGUUACUUAAUCAUACAGUAAGCUGACCUGGAAAUGAAUGAAACUAUUACUCCUAAGAAUUACAUUGUAUAGCCCCACAGAUUAAAUUUAAUUAAUUAAUUCAAAACAUGUUAAACGUUACUUUCAUGUACUAUGGAAAAGUACAAGUAGGUUUACAUUACUGAUUUCCAGAAGUAAGUAGUUUCCCCUUUCCUAGUCUUCUGUGUAUGUGAUGUUGUUAAUUUCUUUUAUUGCAUUAUAAAAUAAAAGGAUUAUGUAUUUUUAACUAAGGUGAGACAUUGAUAUAUCCUUUUGCUACAAGCUAUAGCUAAUGUGCUGAGCUUGUGCCUUGGUGAUUGAUUGAUUGAUUGACUGAUUGUUUUAACUGAUUACUGUAGAUCAACCUGAUGAUUUGUUUGUUUGAAAUUGGCAGGAAAAAUGCAGCUUUCAAAUCAUUGGGGGGAGAAAAAGGAUGUCUUUCAGGAUUAUUUUAAUUAAUUUUUUUCAUAAUUGAGACAGAACUGUUUGUUAUGUACCAUAAUGCUAAAUAAAACUGUGGCACUUUUCACCAUAAUUUAAUUUAGUGGAAAAAGAAGACAAUGCUUUCCAUAUUGUGAUAAGGUAACAUGGGGUUUUUCUGGGCCAGCCUUUAGAACACUGUUAGGGUACAUACGCUACCUUGAUGAAAGGGACCUUCGUGCAACUGUAGUCAUCUUAAAGGCUUCUCAUCCACUGUGCUUCUUAAUGUGUAAUUAAAGUGAGGAGAAAUUAAAUACUCUGAGGGCGUUUUAUAUAAUAAAUUCGUGAAGAAAUGUGUGCUCUUCAGUUCUCAAGUUUUAUUAUUAUGGUAUUUAUUAAAGUUCUACAAUUGUAAUAACGUAUCCAUAUGACAAGUUUUAAAGUGGUAAUUGAAAUAGGUUAUCAGAUAUAGAGUUGUUCACAUCAAGUAGACUUUUAACAGAGUCAGAAUGAACCUACCCUUAAAAUUUUAGAGAAAAAAAAUCGUCGGUUGCACAGAAUAGCUGCUCUAGCUUGCUUAAUUAUGCCGGGCAUGUUGUCACUCCUCUUACUUUUGCUGCCUUUUCAUUACUAUUUAAUGGAAUGUCCCUGAACAAUAAGGAAGAGCAAAACAUAGACAUUUUGACUACAGUGGAUACUUCCUCUACCCCAAAUGUUAUGUUAUAAAAGUACUUUUUUUGCCCAGGUACUCUAUUAUAUAUUUUGGUUUUCUUUGAAUUAGACCUCAAUCUCCAGGAAGCUCUGGAGGGAAAAAAAGGAACCAUAAACUAAAGUAACUGGUUUUCCAAAUAAAUGUAAACUUUUUUAACCUUUUAUUAUUAUAGAACAUUUCAAACAUACAUAAAACAUGAAAACAGCCUGCAGCCAAACUUUUCUGGACCUUGGCAGCUCCAGCAAAUGAGCUGGUCAUCCUAACCCUGGUUUCCUGAGACAACUACUUUUGGGGAUGCUUGCUUGUAUAGGGAGAUGAUAGAUAGAUAGAUACAUAUCAAAAAGAAACUUGAAAAAGGCUUCGAACAGAACUUGCCGAUGUUACUCAUCCCUCCUCGGUACAGACAUUCUGUUAGAACAGAUGGUUGUAAUGGGGCAGCAUCACUCCCUAUUCCCAUUAAAAACAUGACCAUUCUGAGAUUUCAGGCCCCUUCGAGGAAUUUUUCUCAAGAAUUCCAUACAAACUGUCAGAGGAAGAAAUGUCGUCCCAAGACUAGUCCCUGUGUAGUCUUGAUCCCUUUACCUGCUUACUGUAAUUUUUUUUCUCUGACUUUCCGCCAGUGUCUAAGGGCCAUCUGUACCCCUCCCACCCUUCCAUGAGCCACUGUAUAAUCCAAAAACACACCUUCCAUUUGCUCCCUCACUUGUCUCCUUUUACCUCAACAGUGUUAGUGUGUAAAGAAUUGCCUGGGGAGGGUAGAGGGUUUUACAAGUACAGAGUCCCAAGUCUUUUCUCCCCUCCCCGUUAGUGGGUUGGCAUUUAUUAAUAGGCACUGCAAGAUUUUGAUGCAGGUGUGGGGUAGAUAUCACUGUGAAAGGCUACUAAUGCAUGGUAGUUUCACCGAAAGUACAGUCUUCAAGGAUCCUUAUAAUCUCCUCAUUGCCAAAAUCAGUAACAUCUAUAACCUUGACAACACCCUAGCUUGGGCUGUUGCUUCUCUGGCUACUUGUUUUUCCAUCCCAGUUUACCCAGAUUUUAGAUGGAUACUCCUCCAAUUCUGCUUAAAGUCCUUACCUGUUCUUGCCCAGUUCCCUCUAGUCAACCUCAGUCACUCCCAAAGAUUCUUCCCCAAUCCCAUAUCUUUUGCUCAGACCUCUGUCUCUGGGAUUUCUUUGUUACCUCAUAGUCAGUAGUCCUAAAAACAAAAUUCUUCAUCUUGCAUCUCUAUCGACCGACCAUUCUUUGUUUCUUUUUAAGAAAUGUAACCUUCACCCCAAUCAUCAAAAUCUCUCAUUCCUCAAUUGUCACAGGUUGUCACUUCUUUCCCCCUAAACCUCUCCCAUCAUUCCUUCCUUCUUUAUACUGCCCUUACAGGUCCUGAUCCUCUGACUCACCCGGACAUUCUUAGCAGCUGCCUAAUUUCACUCCCUGACUCUCAUCUCCCUCUUCCAAUCCUUUUCAUUGUGCUAGAACACUAUCUUGCUAAUUUUAAUAUCCUCUGCAUUCAGUGCCUCCACAGAUUGCCCCCUCACUGACCUUUCCAAUUUGGCCUUGUGUUACACACUUUCCUCGCUGCAUUCCUACCCAGCAUCUUCACUUGUCAUAUUUCUCAAAUACUCUUCAUGACCAGAUAUUUAAAGUACCUCAUCCAUGAAGACUUCAUCAACCCCCAAAGUGCCUCCAAUGCUUCCGUGGUAGCACAGCAUAAUGGGGUACAUUUCUUAGUUGAACAGUGAGGAGUCACUGGGAUUCUUACAGAGUGUCUUAGGGUCUCCUCUUGAUACUCUUUCCACAUUUCAGUUAAGGAAUUUUCUUACAUCUUUUUUUCUUCUAAUAACCUUUGCCUGGAGUGUAAGUAAAUUCAUGAUAGAGACUGUCAUUUUUAAAAAAAAAAACAAACCAUUUUGCCUUUCACAUGUUAUUACCUCCAUCUUUCUGUUAUCUUGUCAGUGUUGCCACCUAAAUGAUUGAAAAUGACCGAGCAUGCAGUAGAAUGUAGUGAAGUUUCCUAUUUCAUCCAUUUUUUGCAUAAGUGCAUUGGUAUCUGUAUAUCCAUCUGCCCAAGCACCAGUUGUUGAAAAGACUAUUAUUUCCCCAUGAAUGGUCCUGGUACCCUUGUCAAAGAACAGUUGACCAUAAAUAUAAGACUUUCUGGAUUCUCAGUCUUACUCCAUUGCCCUAUAUGUCUGUCGUUAUACCAGCACCGCACUGUCUUGAUGGCUGUAGCUUGGUAGUAAGUUUAGAUUUGGGAUGUGCAAGUCCUCCAUUUUUUUUUUUUUUUUCCCCAAAAUCAUUUUGUCUGUUUUGGGUCCCUUGCAUUGCAUAUGAAUUUUUAUAUGAUCAUUGUGUCAAUUCCUGCAAAACAGCUGGGAUCUUGAUAGGGAUUUAGUUGAAUUGGUAGAUAAAUUUGAGAAAUAACUGCUAUUUUAAUGGUGUUAGGUUUUCUGUUCCAUGACUGUGGGAUGUCUUUGCAUUUGCUUAGGUCUUUAUUUCAGUGAUGUUUUAGAGAUUUCAGUGUGCAAGUCUUGACGUCUUUAAUUUUUUUCUAAGUAUUUUACUGAUGCCACUUUAAUUAUAUGAUUAUUUUCUAAUUUUUAUUUUUGUAUUCAUCACUGGUGUUAGAAAUAAAAUUAAUUUUUGUAUAUUGAUUUUGUAUAUUGUAGCUUUUCUAAAAUUCUUUUUUUGUCACUUAGUAUUUUUUGCAUAUGAGAUCAUGCAUCUGUGAACAGAAAUACUUUUACUUCUUCCUUUCCAGUCUAGAUUCCUAUUAUUUCAUUUUCUUGCCUUAGUGUGCUGGCUAGCACCUCCAGUACAAUAUUGGAUAGAAGUGACAAGAGCAGACAUCUUUUUCUUGUUCCUGAUUUUAAGGGGAAAGCAUUCAGUCUUUCACCAUUGAGUAUGAUGUUAGCUAGCUGUGGGUUUGCUUCAAGUUGAGGAAAUUCUUUUAUUAAACCUAGUUUACUGAGUGUUUUUUAAUCAAAAAAAAAAAAAGGAGGGGCUGUGGGUUUUGUUAAAUGCUUCUUCUGUAUCAAGAUUUUCAUGUUGUUUUGUCCUUUAUUAAUAUGUUGUAUUAAUGGACUUUUGUAUAUUGAAUUAACUUUGCAUUCCUGGGAUAAUCUCAGUUGUCCAUGCUACAUAAACCUUGUUCUAUGCUGCUGGA